AAAGAGAGAGAGAAAAGAAUUCCAACCCAGAAUUCUCAACUUCACUGUGUCAGAACAUAUGAAGUAAACAAAUAUUCAUCUCUACAUUUGCCAGUCCCUGUGGACUUAGACCAGAUAGUAUAAAUAAUAGUCACAAAAGGAGUAUGAAUGGGAUAAGAAGCCACUUCUAGUCUGAGACAAUUAAGAGUAGUAGUGCCUUCUCUGCACUCUCACCGCCUCAUUCUGACAGCUGGAGUGAAGGACUCCCAACUUCUGGAACUGCCCAAUGAAAGUAGCCUUGUGUGAGUGUUAGCUGGCCUGCUUUGGUCUGGGAUGCAAGUAGAAAUAAACUCCUCUCAUAUUAAGCCACUAAGACUUUAGGGAUAUGUUGCUGUAGCAUAGCCUAAUGUAGCCUGAUUACUGAACGAGCCACCCCAUCAACUGAAUCUAUGUAUAUACUAAAAACAUUUUAAGAUAUGCAAGGUCUCAAAGAGUUCACUCGAUGCACACUUUUUCUCAGGAAGCUACUAGAGGAUGUGCUCCACAAAAAAUAAAGGUAUAAAUUGUGAAAGAGGAAAACAUAGGAUUUAGGAAUCAAGGGAAUUCAGCACAAGACAGAAGAAAAGGGAAUCUGCAGCAAGAUCCCUGAGCUGUGCAUGUAACAUAAAGGGCAACAAUUUCCAACACAGAGCAGAUCACAAGACCCUAGGAUAGAUUUCUUGAAGAAAAUGAAAUUAAAAGAAUACUGGAUUCAUCUGAACAUACGAAAAGGAGAUUUAAGCAACUUUUUAAGAGCUUGGGAAUGAAUUAAUGAUAAAUAUAUGGUAUUAUGCAACCAAAACUACAAUAAAAACAUUAAAAAUUAUAACUCAUAAAAUUAUUAAUUUCAGGGAAAAUAAAAAGUUGAGUAGGAAUGAAAAAAGAAUCAGAGGAUACUAUAAAGCUUAUCUGUGGAUAUUGUUUACAUAGUCAUGAUAAUGAAAAAGAAAUAAUCUAACCAAAAUUAAACGUUGGAAGUGUGGGGAGAUAGAAAUGGUAGUGUAUUCGCUAUUUAUGUGUUGGGGAGGAUACCUGUAACUUUAACAUUAGUGAGCUUUACUUUACUAAGGCUAAAUAAACAAACUCAAGUGUCCAGAAAGGCUAGAGAAGGAGCUUAUAAGAAUGAAGCUAUUGUGGUGUGAUUCAAUAGGGAAUAGGUGGGGCCUUGGCAACAUCAAUUUGUAGUAUCCCUGCCAAUUGAUACUACAACAUCAAUUUGUAGUAUCCCUGCCAAAAUUUAACUAUGGAAAAUAGUUAAAUUUUAAUAUGCACACAUCUGUGGUUGUGGUUAUACAGAUAUAUAUAUAUAUAUAUAUAUAUAUAUAUAUAAAAUAAAAAUUUAUAUAUAAAUAAAUACAUAAACAAACUCAAGUGUCCAACAGGGCUAGAUAAGGAGCUUACAAGAAUGAAGCAGUUGUGAUGUGAUUCAAUAGGGAAUAGGUGGGGCCUUGGCAAACCAAAGAACAUAUUCUAUCUAAAGUGGAUGGCCACAACUUGCUCCAGCUGUGGAAACUUGGGCCAUGUACUGCUAGAUCUAAGGAUUUUCUUUUGAGAGAUGCUAGAUAUAUACAUUUUUUAAAAAUAAAAUUAUCCUGAUUUUAACAACAUUGCCUUAUUAUAUAAAACAUACCUUGGAGGGUGUGGGUAAGACACAAUGUCCUUGAAAUUAUAUUUCACUGGGUUAAUAAAAUUGGCUCCGGAAGAAAAUAAUUUUAAACAGCAAACCAAAAAGUGAAGGCCUUCAAAACUAACAAACCAAAGGAAAACAAAACAAAAUGACAACAAGAAAAAAACAAAGAAACAAAACCCCUGGACCUUACCAUUUUUCUAAGGCAUGUUGACAUGAUAAAAUCAAAAUUGCUUUGUGCUUAUAAGGAUCAAAGGUUAUGCUUUUGACUUUAUAAAUUCAGAGAAAGAAUUUAAUUGGAAUUAUUUUUAUGAAUUAACUGAAGAUCUAAGGCAACUGGAUAAUUUAGGUUCUGCUAGUAUCUAGAAUAUUCAAAGUUUAUGUUUAGUCUGACACUAAAGAAUCCAUUAUUUCUCUUGACUUCCAGGCUGGUCAGUGUCUUUCCUGUGUCAUAUACCAAACAAUGUGUUAGAAAUUGUCUUCUCACUCAUAAACUAAUAUUUGUUCAGAGUAAAAAGUCAAGCAAGUAAAUAAUGAGAAAAAAUUCAGUGUAUUGUAUAAACAAAGACAGAAGGCAGACCAAUGGUUACCUGGGGCCUAAGCUAAAGAGAUUAAUUGUACACAGUCACAAAGGAAUUUUUUGGGAUGGUGAAAGUGUUCUAAAACUGGAUUGGGAUGAUUGUGGCACAACUGUAUAAAUGUUAUUAAAACUCAUUGAGUUGUACACUUAAAUGAGUGGCUAAGUUGUGCCUUAAUAAAGCUGUAAUUUUGAAAAAGAAUAAUGGAUGAUCAACUGUGAGCUAGAGUAUGAUGAAAACACAAGACAUUUACAUAGCUUCAAAGUAUCUCCCCAUCAGGUACUUAUUAACUGCAUCAGGGAAACAGUAAUUUUAUUGUGGCAGAACCCUGCUGACAAAGUUAACAUUCUAGUAAAAGCACAGGUGGAUGUCAUGUGCCUCCUGAAGUGAUGCACAGAGAAGGAUGCAACAUCAACUUGUAGUAUCCCUGCCAAAAAUAUAUAACCUGAAUUUAACCAUGCUGAAACAUAAGACAAAUCCAAGUGAAGGAACAUUCUACAAAACAACUGACCAGUACUCCUCAAGAGUGUCAAGGUCCUGGAAGACAAAGACUGAGCAAUGCUUCUGAUUAAAGUAGACUGAGAGGUGACAACUGAAUGCAAUGUGGGAUUCUGGAUUAGGUCUUGGCCCAGAAACAGGUCUUCGGUGGGACAACUGGCAAAAUGUGAAUAAGGUCUCUGGUUUUGUGAAUGGUAGCGUAUCGACACUCAUUACCUGCUUUUGAACAUGGUAGUGAUAGUAAGAUAUCAACAUUCAGGAAAGUACAGUGAAGGGUAUAUGGGAAUCUCUACUAUUUUUGUAACUUUUGUAAGUUGAAAUUGUUUCAAAAUGAGUUAGAAAAUUAAAAGGAAGUUUUCUCUUUCAGCUGGGAAAACAGCAAUGGAUUAAUAAGAAGAAAUUAAUGGUGAAGUGGUGACGAAAAUUCUACAUUGCUUAGAAAGCAAGUAAGAAAAUCAGUGGUUGUAGAGAAGUUCUUACAUGAAGUAAUAAAAAUAAAAAUUGUUAUGUUAAGCAUUUUCUAUUUUCUUUUCCUCCCCUCCAAAUGAAACAGCAUACUAUUCUGCAUGUUUUUCUACCUAACAAUGUAUCUUUUUAAUGACUCUUGUAUUUUAAACCUAAAAUUUUGAUUAAGCUUCACUUAAUAUUAAAAAAGAUAGUAUAGGUCACGAUGUUAUUUGAUGCAAACGUUGGAAAGACAGAAUCUUCUUGAUCCAAGAGCUUUUAGAAUUCAAAGUCUGAUUCUGGUUAUUACUCUGCUCAUUUAAGAUAGUGAAAUGAACAUUUACAUUCUGGCAACCUCAGAAGUACAAAGAACAAAGGACACCAGCCAGGUAGGGCAAAGGCCUGUGCACCCCCUUUUGCUGUUACAUGUUUAUCAGAUGCGUGCUCUGUUUCUGUUAUAUUACAUUACUUUUCUCUUCAAUGUUUACUGAGGAAGAACAAGUAGCUCCUCAGGCAAAUCAACUGUUAACUUUGCUGUUUUUAUUUAAUCUCCCAGGAAUGUAACCCUUAACUUUAAAGAAUGUAGUGACCAUAAAACUUAUAAAGCAUGUUUCUUAAGGAAAUUGUACCUGUUUAUUUAAUCUAUCAGAUAUGAAUGUUAUAGAAAAUUUAAUUUGUCCACUUAAGCUGUAGAUGAACUUUUCACCUUUCUGAUCAGAAAUUCACCAUCUUAUAGUAUAGGUUCUGUUAUUAAUCAGAAUAUUUCAUUUAGACUCUUUCUAUCCAACUUUUUCUUAGAGGCUAUUCAAAAUAAAGGUGCUUCUAACAGUUUCAUAUCGAAAUACGAUGCAAAGCCUUGCUCUUCCAUGGUAUCCUUUGAGUGAGCCAAACUUAUUUAGCCAUUCCCCUAUAGUUAAAUAGCUAGGAUGUUUCCAACAUCUCACCUUUAAAACAAUAGUGCUAUGAAUGUCAUAAAUGUUUGUAUAUGUAAAUAUGUGGGAUAAAUCCCUAUCAGUAGAAUUUCAAAAGGUAUACGCAAUCAGUAUUUUCAUACAUAUUUAAAAUUUUCCAUCCAUACAAAGGUUGCUAACAUAUUUAUUUAAAAUUUUAAAAAUAAUUUUAUAUGCCUCUUGUAACCAGUAAUAGGAUGCAAAGUUUUUUUUUAAGGUAACAUUGCUCCUCUUCCCCCAUUGUCUCUGUCAUCUACAGUACUCCCUGAGGUAGUUCAUGUUAUUGCAAGGGUGUGUAUCAUCACAAACAUAUUGCUUCCACAUACAUAUAUCAGCAUACAUAUAUAUAUAUAUAUGUAUAGCAUAUAUAUAUAUGAGCACAUAUUAAUAUAUGCCCAUGCACAUACAAGCAUGUUUUUGUUAAUUUUUACUGAAAUGGAAUCAUACUACAUACUUAUGAACAAAUUGCUUCUUUCACCUUAUAUCACUUAUAAUUGUUAUUCUACAAAUCAGUACAUAUAAAAAAUACAUAUUUACAUAUGUAAUACUCUAUCUUUCUGUUAUAAUUUUCUGCAUGCACAUGUAUGCAUAUACAUAUAUUCAUAAACAUAAAACUUAAUCUAAACGGGAUUUUUUUUUGGGGGGGUGAUAUGGUUUGGCUGUGUCCCCACCCAAAUCUCAUCUUGAAUUCCCAUGUGUUGUGGGGGGACCCGGUGGGAGGUAAUUGAAUUAUGGGGGCAGGUCUUUCCUGUGCUGUUCUCGGGAUAGUGAAAAAGUCUCACAAGAUCUGAUGGUUUUAAAAAGGUGAGUUUCCCUGCAUAAUCUCUCUUCUCCUGUCUGGUUCCAUGUGAGAUGUGCCUUUUGCCUUCCGCCAUGAUUGUGAGGCCUCCCCAGCCAUGUGGAACCGUAAGUCCAAUAAACCUCUUUCUUUUGCAAAUUGCCCAGUCUCAGGUAUGUCUUUAUCAGCAGCAUAAAAAUGAAACAAUACAGUAAAUUGGUACAAGUAGAGUGGGGCGCUGCUGAAAAGAUACCUGAAAAUGUGGAAGAAACUUUGGAACUGGGCAACAAGCAGAGGUUGGAACAGUUUUGAGGGCUCAGAAGACAGGAAUAUGUGGGAAAGUUUGGAGCUUCCUAGAGACCUGUUGAAUGACUUUGCCCAAAAUGCUGAUAGUGAUAUGGACAAUAAAGUCCAGGCUGAGGUGGUCUUAGAUGGAAACAAGAAACUUGUUGGGAACUGGAGCAAUGGUGACUCUUCUUAUGUUUUAGUAAAGAUACUAGGGGCAUUUUGCCCCUGCCAUAGAUAUAUGUGAAACUUUUAACUUGAGAGAGAUGAUUUAGGGUACCUGGCAGAAGAAAUUUCUAAGCAGCAAAGCAUUCAAGAGGUGACUUGGCUGCUGUUAAAGGUAUUCAGUUUUAUAAGGGAAGCAGAGCACAAAAGUUUGGAAAAUUUGCAGCUUGACAAUGUGCUAGAAAAGAAAAUCCCAUUUUCUAAGGAGAAAUUCAAGCUGGCUGCAGAAAUUUGCAUAAGUAACAAGGAGCUGAAUGUUAAUCCCCAAGACAAUGGGGAAAGUGUCUCCAGGGCAUGUCAGAGUUCUUCAUGGCAACCCCUCCCAUCACAGGCCCAGAGGUUUAGGAGGAAAAAGUGGUUUUGUGGGCUAGGCCCAGGGUCCCUCUGCUGUAUGCAGUCUAGGGACUUCAUACCCUGCAUCCCAGCCAUGAAUGAAAGGAGCCAAAGUACAGCUCUGUCUGUUGCUUCAGAGGGUGCAAGCCCCAAGCCUUGGCAGCUUCCACAUGGCUUUGAGCCUGCGGGUGCACAGAAGUCAAGAAUUGAGGUUUGGGAAACUCUGCCUAGAUAUCAGAAGAUGUAGAAGUUUGCUGUAGGGGUGGGUCCCUCAUGGAGAACCUCUGCUAGGGCAGUGUGAAAGGGAAAUGUGAGAUUGGAGCCCCCAAACAGAGUCCCUACUGGGGCACCAUCUAGUGGAGCAGUGAGAAGAGGGCCACUGUUCUUUAGACCCUGGAAUGGUAGAUCCAUGGACGGCUUGCACUGUGCACCUAGAAAAGCCACAGACACUCAAUGCCAGCCUGUGAAAGCAACCUGGAGAGAGGCUGUACCCUGCAAAACCUCAGGGGCAGAGCUGCCCAAGACCAUAGGAACCAACCCCUUGCAUCAGCAUGACCUGGAUGUGAGACAUGGAGGCAAAGGAGAUCAUUUUGGAGCUUUAAGAUUUGACUGUCCCACUGGAUUUCAGACUUUCAUGGGGCCUGUAUCCCCUUUGUUUUGGCCAAUUUCUCCCAUUUGGGAUGGCUGUAUUUACCAAUGCUGUACCCCCAUUAUAUCUAGGAAGUAACUAACUCGCUUUUGAUUUUACAGGCCCAUAGGUGGAAGGGACUUGCCUUGUCUCAGAUGAGACUUUGGACUUCGGACUGUGGACUUUUGAGUUAACACUGAAAUGAAUUAAUGCUGAAAUGAAUUAAGACUUUGGGAGACGGUUGAGAAGCCAUGACUCAUUUUAAAAUGUGAGAACAUGAGAUUUGGGAGGGGCUGGGGUGGAAUGGUAUGGUUUGGCUGUGUCCCCACCCAAAUCUCAUCUUGGAUUCCCAUGUAUUGUGGGAGGGACCCGGUGGGAGGUAACUGAAUCAUGGGGGCAGGCCUUUCUCAUGCUGUUUUUGUGAUAGUGAACAAGUCUCAUGAGAUCUGAUGGUUUUGAAAAGGGGAGUUUCCCUGCACAAGCUCUCUUCUCUUGUCUGCUUCCAGGUGAGACAUGCCUUUCACCUUCUGCCAUGAUUGUGAGGCCUCUCCAGCCAUGUGGAACUGUGAACACACAUUGUUCAUCCCCUCAGGAGGACACAGCUUUUGAGAUACCAUCUUGGAAGCAGAGACCAGCCCUCACUAGACACAAACUUCCUGGCACCUUGAUUUUGGACUUCAUAGCCUCUAGAACUGUGCUGGGAAGACAACACUUCUGAACUAUAUUUUGACAGAGCAACAUAGUAAAAGAGUAGCGGUCAUUUUAAAUGAAUCUGGGGAAGGAAGUGCGCUGGAGAAAUCCUUAGCUGUCAGCCAAGGUGGAGAGCUCUAUGAAGAGUGGCUGGAACUUAGAAACGGUUGCCUCUGCUGUUCAGUGAAGGACAAUGGCCUUAGAGCUAUUGAGAAUUUGAUGCAAAAGAAGGGGAAAUUUGAUGACAUACUGUUAGAGACCACUGGAUUAGCAGACCCUGGUAUCAUAACUAUUGUGGAUUCAAAAUAUGGAUUAAAACAUUUAACAGAAGAGAAACCUGAUGGCCUUAUCAAUGAAGCUACUAGGCAAGUUGCUUUGGCAGAUAUCAUUCUCAUUAAUAAAACAGACUUGGUCCCAGAAGAAGAUGUAAAGAAAUUAAGAACGACACUUAGAUCCAUAAAUGGACUAGGACAAAUCUUAGAAACACAAAGAUCAAGAGUUGAUCUCUCUAAUGUAUUAGAUCUUCAUGCCUUUGAUAGUCUCUCUGGAAUAAGUUUGCAGAAAAAACUUCAGCAUGUGCCAGGAACACAACCUCACCUUGAUCAGGAAGAAGUAAGGAAAAGAGCAAUAUGGAUGUUUAAAAAUGAGAAGAGUAUUGUUACAAUCACAUUUGACGUACCAGGAAAUGCAAAGGAAGAACAUCUUAAUAUGUUUAUUCAGAAUCUUCUGUGGGAAAAGAAUGUGAGAAACAAGGACAAUCACUGCAUGGAGGUCAUAAGGCUGAAGGGAUUGGUGUCAAUCAAAGACAAAUCACAACAAGUGAUUGUCCAGGGUGUCCAUGAGCUCUGUGAUCUGGAGGAGACUCCAGUGAGCUGGAAGGAUGACACUGAGAGAACAAAUCGAUUGGUCCUCAUUGGCAGAAAUUUAGAUAAGGAUAUCCUUAAACAGCUGUUUAUAGCUACUGUGACAGAAACAGAAAAGCAGUGGACAACACAUUUCAAAGAAGAUCAAGUUUGUACAUAACACUAGAGGCAUUUCUUAUCAAAAGGAUUGGAUAAUAAAAAUAAGUUUCUACUGGGUAUAUUUCAAGCAUUUAUUUAUUACUUUAGUUACGAAUUCCAAUAUACUUUAAAAUGGUAUUUGUUUUACAGCAUACAUAAAAUGUAGCAAAUCAGUACUGUAAAACAUUUAACAUUCAUACAAUUAUAUACAAUAUCCUUUUUUUUAAAGAAUGGUAUUUCACAAAAAUAUCUUUUGAAAUUGGCUUUGGAGUUUACAUAUACUGAACAUGAAAGUUUAUAAUAAUGAUGAUACAACUUUCAACAUUGUCAUUUUUUCUUAGAACUUCAGCUGAUUGCAGAGAUAUAAUGAUUACAUUGUUAUUAAAUUUUUUUAACACAAGUAAGUGUCACCAUUUUAUGACAUGAAAUAAAAGGUUAUGACUGUUA